GCUACUCGGGGGUAGGGCUGCGGAGGGGAUCUAGUGUGUAAUAAGGGGGAUCAGGGCUUUCAUGAAGGGAUCUAAGUGUGAACCAACAAGGAUUAUAUCUGUGGAGAUAUCUCUGAGCAGAGAGCAAUAGAGGACAGGAAUGUGUGAUGAUCUCGGUGUGCUAAAGUGGAUUACAGCUAGGGAGGGCUGAAGUGUGUGCUAAUGGGAGUCAGGGCUGAAUGAGACCUGUGUGCACUAAUGAGGGUCAGGCCAUGGUAGAACAGUGUGUUUGUGUGUCCCUGCGGAAUAGGGCUGAGUAAGGGUUCAGGGUGCACUAAUGGGGAGGCAGGACUGUGUGAGGCCCGGCGUGUGCUAAUAGAAAUCAGGCCUGAGUGAAGACUCAGUUUGUGCUGACAGAGGGGACAGGACAGUGGAAGGACUGGAAUGUGUGUUAAGGAUGGUCGUAGCUGUGAAGGGGCCUGAGUGUGGGUAACACUGGUUAGAGAUCUAUCUGUAAGGUUCACUUUAUGUUAAUAGCAUUCAGAGCAGCAUGAAGAAGGUCCAGUGAGUGCUAAUGUGGGUCAGCUAUAGAGUACCCCAAGUGCAUGUUAAUAGAGGUCAGAAUCAUGUAGGGGGAACAGUACGUUAAUGAGGGGAGUCAGUACUAUGGAGAAGGUAACAAGCAGCUAGGCCAGGGAGGGGCCCAAGAAUGUGGUGGCAAGAGUUACUUAGAGGAGGCUAAGUGUGUGCUGACAGAGUUCAGGGCGGUAUGUUAUGUGUUAGGGCUUUGAAUGCUGAUGGGUAUAUGAGAUAAUAGCAGGUAAGAUGUAGUGAGGCCUCCUUGAGGGUCUAGCGUGUAUUAAUGGGGAUCAGGACAUAGGGUGCGAUGACCAAGUCCUUAGUGGUUGGUGUGUUGAGUAUCCUUGAGUAUGAGAGUAGUCUGAGGAUGGGUGUAUGUCUUUGGGGAUCAGGAAGGGUCAGGCAGGACAUGUGCCUUUUUUGGGGUAAGGUUUUAUGUCCAGUUUCUUGCUCCCUCCUUUUUUGAAAUCUAAAAAGCUCAUUCAACUGAAAUGAUAUUUAAAAGUUUCCUUGCGUAUAAAUGUUCAAUUAUCUCUGUUCACAGGGGCAUGUCUGAGACCCCCAUCCCCCUUUCUGGGAGUGUUAUGUGAUAUACAGAUUUUACACCCCAUCUUCCUAAAAUCCCAAAAAACUGAACUCCAGAGCAUGUCCAGCCCUUGGGGUUUCCAGUUAGAGGUCGUGGACCCAUGGCUCCUCCUGGCUUCCUCCCCAUCCUCCAUUCAGCCCUACUUCCAGUCUCCCCCAGCCCCUCCCCUACUCCCUGUCACAACAUGCAAAGCAACUGGGUAUCUGUGCCAUAUGGGGACACAAGGUUGUCUUUGGGAGCUGGCCAUGCUUUACCUUCCUUGCCUUAGGCCCAGUAUUCAGCCUCCCAGGUCAGGAUGUUUUGUGGUUAUCCUGGGUUCUCCAUGGAUGGACCUCAUCCUGUAUCUGAGGUCUUUCUGCUAGGGUGGCCCCUACCCCUCCUGGGGAUAGUGAGUUCAGCCAGGUGGGGGCGAGAACUGCUGGGGGAAGCACCUGAUUUCAAGGUAGCAGAUGACCCAUUUCUCUCCUCAAAUCCAGCCCCAGUCUCAUCCUCGACCUCCUAUCUAGCUCUACUUCCCUUGGGCCCAGGGCCAUCUUAGGCCCUGCUGUGAGUCCAGAUGGUUCCUGGGUCAGGUCUUUCCCCCUCCUUGCUGGCCCAGAGCCCAAGAGGAAGCAGAAGACGGCUGGCCUAAGCCUUUUGGUGGCCCCAUUCCCUUCAGCAAUCCAUCUAGGUCAUCUUCCUGUCGAUGCCAGCAUCCCUGGGCUACCUUGUUUAGGGUUGUUCAAUGAAUAGCAGGGACUCAUCACCUCAGCAGAGGUUGGUCCUAGGCCCUCAGCCCCCUGAUUCACUUAUUUCUGCCAUAAGCACUUUUUGAGCAUCUACUCUGUGUCAGUCACUAUUCCAGGUCCUCAGGAUAUAGCCGUGACCUAAACACAGAAAUCUACCCUGGCGGAGCUGAUCUUCUAGUUGUGGCGGUGAGGAGAUAGACAGUAAAGACUAAAGAAACCAAUAAAUCGCCAUGGAUCGGAUGAAGAAGAUCAAACGGCAGCUGUCAAUGACACUCCGAGGUGGCCGAGGCAUAGACAAGACCAAUGGUGCCCCUGAGCAGAUAGGCCUGGAUGAGAGUGGUGGUGGUGGCGGCAGUGACCCUGGAGAGGCCCCCACACGUGCUGCUCCUGGGGAACUUCGUUCUGCACGGGGCCCACUCAGCUCUGCACCAGAGAUUGUGCACGAGGACUUGAAGAUGGGGUCUGAUGGGGAGAGUGACCAGGCUUCAGCCACGUCCUCGGAUGAGGUGCAGUCUCCAGUGAGAGUGCGUAUGCGCAACCAUCCCCCACGCAAGAUCUCCACUGAGGACAUCAACAAGCGCCUAUCACUACCAGCUGACAUCCGGCUGCCUGAGGGCUACCUGGAGAAGCUGACCCUCAAUAGCCCCAUCUUUGACAAGCCCCUCAGCCGCCGCCUCCGUCGUGUCAGCCUAUCUGAGAUUGGCUUUGGGAAACUGGAGACCUACAUUAAGCUGGACAAACUGGGCGAGGGUACCUAUGCCACCGUCUACAAAGGCAAAAGCAAGCUCACAGACAACCUUGUGGCACUCAAGGAGAUCAGACUGGAACAUGAAGAGGGGGCACCCUGCACCGCCAUCCGGGAAGUGUCCCUGCUCAAGGACCUCAAACACGCCAACAUCGUUACGCUACAUGACAUUAUCCACACGGAGAAGUCCCUCACCCUUGUCUUUGAGUACCUGGACAAGGACCUGAAGCAGUACCUGGAUGACUGUGGGAACAUCAUCAACAUGCACAACGUGAAACUGUUCCUGUUCCAGCUGCUCCGUGGCCUGGCCUACUGCCACCGGCAGAAGGUGCUACACCGAGACCUCAAGCCCCAGAACCUGCUCAUCAACGAGAGGGGAGAGCUCAAGCUGGCUGACUUUGGCCUGGCCCGAGCCAAGUCAAUCCCAACAAAGACAUACUCCAAUGAGGUGGUGACACUGUGGUACCGGCCCCCUGACAUCCUGCUUGGGUCCACGGACUACUCCACUCAGAUUGACAUGUGGGGUGUGGGCUGCAUCUUCUAUGAGAUGGCCACAGGCCGUCCCCUCUUUCCGGGCUCCACGGUGGAGGAACAGCUACACUUCAUCUUCCGUAUCUUAGGAACCCCAACUGAGGAGACGUGGCCAGGCAUCCUGUCCAACGAGGAGUUCAAGACAUACAACUACCCCAAGUACCGAGCCGAGGCCCUUUUGAGCCACGCACCCCGACUUGAUAGCGACGGGGCCGACCUCCUCACCAAGCUGUUGCAGUUUGAGGGUCGAAAUCGGAUCUCCGCAGAGGAUGCCAUGAAACAUCCAUUCUUCCUCAGUCUGGGGGAGCGGAUCCACAAACUUCCUGACACUACUUCCAUAUUUGCACUAAAGGAGAUUCAGCUACAAAAGGAGGCCAGCCUUCGGUCUUCGUCGAUGCCUGACUCAGUUGCCGGUGGACAGCAUGGCCGUGCCAGCCUCCCACACUGAGGCCAGGUCUACCCCCCAUCAUACCAGCCCCCAGGACCACUACCCCACGGCCAGCCAGGGGUCCAGAGCUAGCCCAGGCUGGGGAUCUCGACUCAGACAAGAUGGUGACAAUGCCUUGAGUCUGAGGCAUCCUCUGCCUGCUUUCCUGCCUGCCCCACCUGCCUCAUAUUGUGUGGGCCUUUUUUUGUUUGUUUCAUUCAUUGUUUUUUUUUUUUUAAUUAUUUUAAAUGAGAUUUUUGUUUUUUUUAAAUGCAAUAUCUCUGUAUACAGACUGGCUGGGCCCCACCCCCUGCGUGUGGCCCUCCCACAGUAUUUUGUGCAAUGAAGCCCUGCUCCCAGCCUUUCAGAGACAGGGACACAGCCCCUAUUUGGAACCCUGAUCAUCACCAGACCCUGGGAUUGGCUAUGGGAAAGCAUGCCACAGCCACUCGCCUUCCUACCCCCGCCCGCCAUCCCCAGUUGCAGGGGGAUCUGGGGACUACCAGAGACUCUGGGAAAUGGACAAGGUGGGGGGCCCCACUCUUUCUCUCCUGCAGUCCCGUAGCUGGGGCCUCCUUCCUUCUCAGGGUCUCCCCAGCCCAGUCCCCUUGCUCCCAUCCCACUCGGUGCUGUUGGGUAGGGGCCCUGCCAGGAACUGACCAGCUCAGCGAGGAGCCAUAAUGUGCAUAUGUGCACAAGCAGGGUUGGGGGAGGGGGGUGUGAGGGGUUGUGCCCAGGUGUUGCCCCCUAUCUCCUGGGGAGGGUGAGGCAGGGCAGGGACAGUCUCCAGGGUCAGUCCCUGGAUGGGUGGUUACCUCCCCUUCCUCCACCCUAAGCCCUGGGGCCCUGAAAUGGGGUGGGAGGGCAGGGGUGGGAGCCCUCCUAGUGGGUUUGGGGGGUUGGGUUCCUGAAUGCACCAUAAUCGCUGUAUGAAAUAUUAAAAAGUCUAAAGUGAAAA